AAAAUUUGCUGAUUAAAUGAAUGUGGGUGUGUUUGAGAGGGAUCCUAGACAGCCAAGCCUUCUGGCAUGAAACGCUGAGAAGAUGGGAGUGUCUGCUGGCAGAGAUGAAAGUGAGCAGGGGUGAGCGCAGCCACUGCCCAACGCAAACCGUGAAGAAGCUUCUGGAAGAGCAGAGGCGCCGCCAGCAGCAGCAGCCCGACGCUGGCGGGGUGCAGGGACAAUUUCUCCCUCCCCCAGAGCAGCCCCUGACCCCAUCUGUGAAUGAGGCUGUGACUGGCCACCCUCCCUUCCCAGCACACUCGGAGACUGUGGGUUCUGGACCUAGCAGCCUGGGCUUUCCAGACUGGGACCCCAACACGCAUGCUGCCUACACUGACAGCCCCUACUCUUGCCCUGCUUCUGCUGCCGAAAAUUUCCUGCCUCCUGACUUCUACCCACCCUCGGACCCAGGGCAGCCGUGCCCAUUUCCCCAGGGCAUGGAGGCUGGACCCUGGAGAGUUUCUGCACCCCCUUCAGGACCCCCACAGUUCCCCGCUGUGGUCCCUGGACCAUCGCUGGAGGUGGCCCGAGCUCACAUGCUGGCUUUGGGGCCACAGCAGCUGCUGGCCCAGGAUGAGGAGGGGGACACGCUCCUUCACCUGUUUGCGGCUCGGGGGCUGCGCUGGGCGGCAUAUGCUGCGGCUGAGGUGCUCCAGGUGUACCGGCGUCUUGACAUUCGUGAGCAUAAGGGCAAGACCCCUCUCCUGGUGGCGGCUGCUGCCAACCAGCCCCUGAUUGUGGAGGAUCUGUUGAACCUGGGAGCAGAGCCCAAUGCCGCUGACCAUCAGGGACGUUCGGUCUUGCACGUGGCCGCUACCUACGGGCUCCCAGGAGUUCUCUUGGCUGUGCUUAACUCUGGGGUCCAGGUUGACCUGGAAGCCAGAGACUUCGAGGGCCUCACCCCGCUCCACACGGCCAUCCUGGCCCUUAACGUUGCUAUGCGCCCUUCCGACCUCUGUCCCCGGGUGCUGAGCACACAGGCCCGAGACAGGCUGGAUUGUGUCCACAUGUUGCUGCAAAUGGGUGCUAAUCACACCAGCCAGGAGAUCAAGAGCAACAAGACAGUUCUGCACUUGGCCGUGCAGGCUGCCAACCCCACUCUGGUUCAGCUGCUGCUGGAGCUGCCCCGGGGAGACCUGCGGACCUUUGUCAACAUGAAGGCCCACGGGAACACAGCCCUCCACAUGGCGGCUGCCCUGCCCCCUGGGCCGGCCCAGGAGGCCAUCGUGCGGCACCUGUUGGCAGCUGGGGCGGACCCCACACUGCGCAACCUGGAGAAUGAGCAGCCCGUUCACCUGCUGCGGCCCGGGCCGGGCCCUGAGGGGCUCCGGCAGCUGUUGAAGAGGAGCCGUGUGGCGCCGCCAGGCCUGUCCUCUUAGGACUCAAACCCAGACCCUGGACUGAUUUUCCAGUCCCCACCGUCCUGCGGGACAGCCAGCGUAUGCUAAUGUUGCAAACCCAUGAUAAUGUAUGUGGAAUAUCCUGCCAUUGGGGUUUUACAUUAAAACCCCAGAAUGGCUGCAGAGGGGUGAACAGGCCCCAAUAUUUGGGGUGCUGUGAUACCCCUCUUCUACCCACAAGGAGCCCUCUUGAUGAUUUCUGUGAAAUCGAGGCCCCUUGAUUGUUUCUGUGAAACACCCUGCACCCCUAGUCCUUUCCCCACUGAGAUCUUUCGGGUUCUCUCCCCUAACUCAGCUCUUCGUUCCCAGAAACCCAGAUGUAAUCCCCCUACGUGGUGCUUGGGGCAUCCCGAUACCAUCUCAGUAAAUCUCCUACAAUGGCCUCCUCACCCUCCCCGGGACCCACACCCUUCAGGUCCUCACCCUGAGACAGGAGGGACCCUCUGAGAUCAGGGACCCUUAGGUCUCACUGCUCUCUGAUUCAGAGCUCAGCUGGGCCCCCAGUUCCAGACCCCAGCAUUCCCGGUCACUCCCUCCCUAAUCUGAGCAUCACUCAAGCUCUUUAUUAAACUCAAUUUGGGCCAGA